GUCAUUCCCCUGCGCUCUCUUUCCUCACCCUUCCCCCCGCCACCGUGGGUUCCAGACUUGGGAUAAGUAAACAGCGGGUGGAGCGAGGCCUACGGACCCAGGCCAGGUGGGAGUCUGCACUCUUCAAGGGGCCUGGGCUGCUGCUCACGGGUAUUAAAGAACUCCGCGUUGUUCAUGGCUGAGGCGAUGCAUUAGGAAGAUCCUGGACCUAGAGAACAAGUCCCCCGAACGCUGAGUUGGAGGCGGGACUUCGGGUGCGCGUUGGCGGGAGCAUGCUGGGGCUCUGGGGGCAGCGGCUCCCCGCGGCGUGGGUCCUGCUUCUGUUGCCUUUCCUGCCGCUGCUGCUGCUUGCAGCCCCCGCGCCCCACCGCGAGUCCUACAAGCCGGUCAUCGUGGUGCAUGGGCUCUUCGACAGCUCGUACAGCUUCCGCCACCUGCUGGAAUACAUCAAUGAGACACACCCCGGGACUGUGGUGACAGUGCUCGAUCUCUUCGAUGGGAGAGAGAGCUUGCGACCCCUGUGGGAACAGGUGCAAGGGUUCCGAGAGGCUGUGGUCCCCAUCAUGGCAAAGGCCCCUCAAGGGGUGCAUCUCAUCUGCUACUCGCAGGGGGGCCUUGUGUGCCGGGCUCUGCUUUCUGUCAUGGAUGAUCACAACGUGGAUUCUUUCAUCUCCCUCUCCUCUCCACAGAUGGGACAGUAUGGAGACACGGACUACUUGAAGUGGCUGUUCCCCACCUCCAUGCGGUCUAACCUCUAUCGGAUCUGCUAUAGCCCCUGGGGCCAGGAAUUCUCCAUCUGCAACUACUGGCAUGAUCCCCACCACGAUGACUUGUACCUCAAUGCCAGCAGCUUCCUGGCCCUGAUCAAUGGGGAAAGAGACCAUCCCAAUGCCACAGUAUGGCGGAAGAACUUUCUGCGUGUGGGCCACCUGGUGCUGAUUGGGGGCCCUGAUGAUGGUGUUAUUACUCCCUGGCAGUCCAG